AGUAACCAGGGACGACCGCGGCCACACCGCGCCGGCGCCGGCGCCCAGCCCAGGCAGCCCCGCGCCGCGGCGCCCGGACCGCCCGGGCCUGCCCAGCGGCCGCCCCACGCCCCGGGCGCCCCGGCGCCGACAGCCGCGCAGCGCAGCGCGGGCGCCGCAGACAAAGGCGCGGCCCCGGCCCGGCCCGCCCGGCCCAGCCGCUCCUGCUGGGCGCCCCAACCGGGUCCGGCCCGGGGGGGCGGGGGCCGCGGCCGCCGAGGAUGGGGAAAUCCAACAGCAAGUUGAAGCCCGAAGUUGUGGAGGAGCUGACCAGGAAGACCUACUUUACCGAGAAGGAGGUCCAGCAGUGGUACAAAGGCUUCAUCAAGGACUGCCCCAGUGGGCAGCUGGAUGCGGCAGGCUUCCAGAAGAUCUACAAGCAAUUCUUCCCGUUCGGAGACCCCACCAAGUUUGCCACAUUUGUUUUCAACGUCUUUGAUGAAAACAAGGACGGGCGAAUUGAGUUCUCCGAGUUCAUCCAGGCGCUGUCGGUGACCUCACGGGGAACCCUGGAUGAGAAGCUACGGUGGGCCUUCAAGCUCUACGACUUGGACAAUGAUGGCUACAUCACCAGGAAUGAGAUGCUGGACAUUGUGGAUGCCAUUUACCAGAUGGUGGGGAAUACCGUGGAGCUCCCAGAGGAGGAGAACACUCCUGAGAAGAGGGUGGACCGGAUCUUUGCCAUGAUGGAUAAGAAUGCCGACGGGAAGCUGACCCUGCAGGAGUUCCAGGAGGGUUCCAAGGCAGACCCGUCCAUUGUGCAGGCGCUGUCCCUCUACGACGGGCUGGUAUAGUCCCAGGCUGGAGCUGGAUGCCUGGGAACCACUCACCUCCUUCUGUGCCAUGAGGCCACCUCAGCCCUGACACCAACCCCGUGCGUCCACCCAGCCUUCUUCCGCAUCCACACACAGCCGGCUGCCCUUGACCCGGGAGGCCCCGGCUCUCCUCUCCCCUGUCCUGCACCCAUCCCCCGCCUGAAGCCACCGGCUCCAAUUGCCAGCAACCUCUGCUUGUCCGGAAAACGACAACACGAAAUGGAAAAGGCUACAGCCCUCUGCAUAAACCAAGGACUUGGCUGCCUCGCAGGCAGCCUCCGUUCCUCCCGCUCUCUUGCGCGUGUGCUUUUGUUUUUUAUUUUGAACAGACGUUUUAAAAGAAAAAAAAACAACUACCUUCUGUCCUAGAAGACACAGACUGACAGAUGGGGUGAAGGCCUGGGGACCUCAGAGAACUCUGCCUUGCCCUCGUCCCUCGUCCUUCGGCAGCCGGAGAGGCUGUGGGUGGGCCGAGGGUGUCUAGGGGUUCUGCCUGGUCAACGUUAUUUGUCGUCCCAUCUUUUGGCAGCAAAACCACCUGCGUGGCUAGGAUGAUUAAUUAUGAGGAUGAUGAUUUUUUUUGUGAUAACAGUAUUGUGCUUUUUGUGGGGAAAGUGAGGUUUUUUUUUAUAUACAUAUAUAAUUGAUAUCUUUAAUUUAUUGGUUGUUAACUGUUGCUGCUGCCUGGUGUGUCCUCAGCUCCCAGGGCUGCGGGCCCACCGUUUACAUGUGCACGCCCUGACCCACCUGCCCACGCCGACUUGGGAGGAUGGUGGCCUGCAGCGGCCAAGAAGCCAAAAAAAAUUUUUUUUUUUUCAGAUACUGUGCUUGAUUUUUGGAGAGGGGAGAGGUGGAAAUUCCUAAAUGGCUAAUGCACUGUUCCCUCCAGCCCGAAUGCCUCCUGCCAAACCCCUUUUCCCUGCUGCCUCUGUCCCCGCAUCCUUGUUCUCCCCUGGGUCCGUAACAUUUUUUCCGAGGAUGAACAGGGGACAUCUUUAGGUUUCUCAACUCUUGCUUUGGUGUUUGCCGCAGCAUGGAAAACAGGGCGCCUAAGGCUGGGAGCUGGAAGAAGGGGCAUUGGGUACCCAGGCAGAGUCAGGAGAGGUGGUCUUUGAAGUAAGUUAGCAGAAAUCAAGGGGACCCCCGCCUCCUUGGGCUGGGGAGGGGAUUUCAAGAUAGUUCAUGACUCUCUCCCGCUCUGCCUUCCCUCCUUCCUAUCUGCUUUUUCCAGUAAACUGCAUGGUGUCCUUCCCUGGCCUUCUCUUGGCUCAAAGGCUGGGAGGGAGGGAAGGAGAGAAGAGUUCCAGGCAAUCCCAUCAAUAUAGUCCCUACACCUGGGGCUGCGGCCCACAUGUCUUCACGGAGGCUUCCAGCGGUGCCUGCCACUGAGGCAGGUGCGGCCCCAGGACCAUCACCAGGAAUGCGAGGCCACCCUGGACCAGAGGUAGGAGCCCAAGGUCCGGCCCUUGCUCUUUGAUUGUGGGCAGCCUCCUGCCCUCUCUGGGUCUCAGUUGCCCCAUCUGCAGAGCGAGGAGGCCCGGGCUGGUUGGUCUUGAAGGCCCUUUUCCAUGCCGACAUCAUGUCACUCUAGGCCUGGGGUUCAGUUUCCUGUGGCUGGUGAUGCUGUGGUUAAGUUUGCUUGACCCCAGCAGCCCGAGGGACUGUCUGAGUCACAGCACAGCCCCUAUUGCGUGGCUGCUGGUGUGUGGGGUCAGUUCCAGCAGAUGAAUGUGUCAUGUGGCACACCUUGUCCCUUCCCGCAGCAUUUCCUGGUUCCCCCCAGACCCUUGAGCGCUCUUUGGGACCCAGAAGGAGUCCUUGCACAGGGAAGGCUUGAGGUGAGAAGCCGCUUCCCAGACUGUCAGGGCCAGGCCUGGGUCUAGAAUUCUUGCUGCUGCUUUGCAGAGUCAACAGCCCAUCAGCCCAUGUUUUAGAGGGGACACUUUGGUCCUCGGUUCCCACCCUCAGCAAGCAGGCCUCCAGCCCGAGGAAGGCCUCUGCCGUAGUGACGUUGCCGUGUGGGGCUGCGUGGCUGUUCCCCUUGGCUGGAGCAUUCAGCCAACCCCAGCGUCCCCCCUGAGGCGUUCAUUGGCAGCCCCCUAGGACUGCACGCUGGCCCCACGGUAACCCCCCCUCCCCCACCAACAUCCUGCAGGGAUGGGGUCAGUGGUUCCACCUUCACAGGCCACUUUGAAGGGUGGAUUCUUUGAGGCCCCUGCCAGUCGGCUCCCUGCUCAGCUGCUGGCCCGGGCGACCUGGGACUCAGCACCAACGGCUGAAGUUUCUCAGCUGGGCUCUGACCUGGGGUCUGGGGCAGGGAACGAACAUGGUGGCUUUGGGCUGAGAGGAUGAGGGAGGUCUUUCCCAGGUCAAAUUACUUUCCUUUGGCCUCUGCCUGAGGCUCGAUUUGCCUCUCUGGUCCAAUGGGACUGACACUGUUGUACAACCUGACCUGUGGCUGAGGGUGUCUGGGCUUAAGCAUGUGGACCCCUUCGGUGUGUCCGGCCUUCCUCCAUCGUCCUGCCCUUUGGCCUUUUGGUUUGAAGCCACAGGUGUGGCUUCUGGCCUUAGCAGAUGGUAUGCUUGCGGACCGCAGCCCAGCAUGCCGGUGGGCCCACAGCCCGAGCCAGCCCAGAGCUGCCGGAAGGGCCGCCCUUCCCGGCCCUGGCGGGGUGCUGGACACUGGCCAUUUUCACUAGAGUUUGCCUGGCAGGGACCGAUCUCUGCCCCCUCCUCUCCCCAGGCCUCUGGCUGCAGUGAUGCCGCAGAAUCCUGAGCCAGGUGCCUCCUGAGCAGCCCGUGCGCCUCUCCACAGCGGCGUUUGCCACCCAAUGCGGCUCGCUUCAGAUGCUCUGAUGCAGAGGGCACGCCCAUAGUCCCUCUGCAGAGCCUCGCACUGGGGCCAGGGCAGGCACCAGCCCCAGGCGGCCAGUCGGCCACGGCCUGUCCUCUUCCUCGUAGCGUCUGCUCCUCACUUUGUGUUGAUGGUGACUUAGGAGAAUGUUCCGAUUUUCCAUGAUCUAAGCAGGCCACGUUUAAAAUAACAUCAAGGCAAGCGUACGUGUCACCCUCUGUACUGACAUCUCUUCCCCUGAAAUGCUUUUCAGUUUGACAGCCCGUUUCCUAGACAAGUGCACCUGGGGUUUCAGGAACUUUGUGUUUUUUCGGAGGGGGUUGGUGGGGAGGUCGGGAUGCCUGGGAUCCCUUCCUGGAGAGGCAGGCUGUCUCUGGAAAAAGCCUCCAUUGCCCACCCGCCAGGCGGAAAGUCACCCUGUUCCCAGCGCGGUUUCAGCAUUUAAUUUUAAGGGAGCUAAGGAAGCGCGGCGCGCCCCCUGGUGGUGGUAAGCCGCCAACGCACCUGGGGGCUGCAACCCCACCGGACGGGUGGUCCGGAGGGAGGCUGGAGCGGGGAGGCGAGGAGGGGGCUGUGAGUCCUCAGAGGCCCUGGGCCACCACAUUUCUGGCAGCGUUUCCCAGACACCCCUCUGCUAGGCCAUCCCUGGAUAGCAAGUGAAUUAACUUAAGGGCACUGUGAUGGGAAGCCUUGCCCCCCUCUUUUUUUUUUUUUUUUAAUAUCUGCGGAAUAAACCCAAUGGUUAAUUUUUGAAUGAAUAAAAGGCUUUUGUUGAAUAAACAGCUGGUCCCAUCUUCUGUCUUGGCAUCUUAGCAUCCAGGCUCAGGCUCUGCCCCUUCUCCAGGAUGGGGUAGCCCCGAGUCGCCCUCCCCAGUCUGCACAUUCCCUGUUGUCCCUGUUCCUGCAGUGGCUCCCGGCCCCAGGGAGGCCCACCUCACUCCCAGCCUGACUCGGUGGCUGGCUUCCUUCAGGACUUUGCGCAAGUCAGUUCUGCUCAUUGGGUCUCAAUUUCCCCAUCCCUUGGAUGGGAGCAAGAGUCUCUGCUGGGCCUGCCUCGCAGGGGCCUGGUGAGACCCAAAUGUGAGUGUCAUCAUCAAAGCCCCUCACAGAAGUGGAGGACGGUGCCCAAGAGUAGCGGUUUGGACUGCUGCUGCCUCCCACCCGGAGCCUGCCACUUGGGGGAGAAAUUGGUAUAAUGCUUGCAAAAACAAACAAACAAAAGGCAAUGUCUUCUGGUUGUGGUUAUUUCCUUUCCUGCUUGCCUCCCCAGCCCCCUUUGAGUCUCUUUUUGGGGUGCCGUCCUGUCUGAACCUGCCGGUGUGUGUCUCUGGGGCCAGGGUCAGGGCGAGGCCCAGGGGUGGACAGGGGCCGUGUAGCAUGCCCCAGCCUCCCCAAGCUCCUGCUGUAUGUCGUCCAUGUCACGCCAAUUAAACACGCUUCCUGGACUUGUCCUCGC